AGAUGCAGCGGAGUCUGAGCUCUGCUGCAUCUGUCACAGCAGAACAAAAUUAAAAACACAACAGUGGAAGAGAAACGCUGCAGACUAUGGGACGCUGUAGGACUUUCUAAAACAUUUGCUGGGGAUUUCUGUGAAGCAUGAUCUUUUAAAACGAAUUCUUUUGGAAGCCGGUUUGGGUAACUGGGAAAAUGACACAUAUGCUAAAUGCAGCAGCUGAUCGAGUGAAAUGGACCAGAUCGAGUGCUGCUAAGAGGGCUGCCUGCCUGGUGGCUGCGGCAUAUGCUCUGAAAACCCUCUAUCCCAUCAUUGGCAAGCGUUUAAAGCAAUCUGGCCACGGGAAGAAAAAAGCAGCAGCUUACCCUGCUGCAGAGAACACAGAAAUACUGCAUUGCACCGAGACCAUUUGUGAAAAACCUUCGCCUGGAGUGAAUGCAGAUUUCUUCAAACAGCUACUAGAACUUCGGAAAAUUUUGUUUCCAAAACUUGUGACCACUGAAACAGGGUGGCUCUGCCUGCACUCAGUGGCUCUAAUCUCAAGAACCUUUCUUUCUAUCUAUGUGGCUGGUCUGGAUGGAAAAAUCGUGAAAAGCAUUGUGGAAAAGAAGCCUCGGACUUUCAUCAUCAAAUUAAUCAAGUGGCUUAUGAUUGCCAUCCCUGCUACCUUCGUCAACAGUGCAAUAAGGUACCUGGAAUGCAAAUUGGCUUUGGCCUUCAGAACUCGCCUAGUAGACCACGCCUAUGAAACCUAUUUUACAAAUCAGACUUAUUAUAAAGUGAUCAAUAUGGAUGGGAGGCUGGCAAACCCUGACCAAUCUCUUACGGAGGAUAUUAUGAUGUUCUCCCAAUCUGUGGCUCACUUGUAUUCCAAUCUGACCAAACCUAUUUUAGAUGUAAUGCUGACCUCCUAUACACUCAUUCAAACUGCUACAUCCAGAGGAGCAAGCCCAAUUGGGCCCACCCUACUAGCAGGACUUGUGGUGUAUGCCACUGCUAAAGUGUUAAAAGCCUGUUCUCCCAAAUUUGGCAAACUGGUGGCAGAGGAAGCACAUAGAAAAGGCUAUUUGCGGUAUGUGCACUCGAGAAUUAUAGCCAAUGUAGAAGAAAUUGCCUUUUACAGAGGACAUAAGGUAGAAAUGAAACAACUUCAGAAAAGUUACAAAGCUUUAGCAGAUCAGAUGAACCUCAUUUUAUCCAAACGUUUGUGGUACAUCAUGAUAGAACAGUUCCUGAUGAAGUAUGUUUGGAGCAGCAGUGGACUAAUUAUGGUGGCUAUACCUAUUAUCACUGCAACUGGCUUUGCAGAUGGUGAGGAUGGCCAAAAGCAAGUUAUGGUUAGUGAACGGACAGAAGCCUUUACCACUGCUCGAAAUUUACUGGCCUCUGGAGCUGAUGCUAUUGAAAGGAUUAUGUCUUCAUACAAAGAGGUCACUGAAUUAGCAGGCUACACUGCUCGAGUGUACAAUAUGUUUUGGGUCUUUGAUGAAGUAAAAAGAGGCAUUUAUAAGAGAACUGCUGUCAUUCAAGAAUCUGAAAGCCAUAGCAAGAAUGGAGCUAAGGUAGAAUUACCUCUCAGUGACACAUUGGCAAUUAAAGGAAAAGUUAUUGAUGUGGAUCACGGAAUUAUUUGUGAAAAUGUUCCCAUAAUUACACCAGCAGGAGAAGUGGUGGCUUCCAGGCUAAACUUCAAAGUAGAAGAAGGAAUGCAUCUUUUGAUAACUGGUCCCAAUGGUUGUGGGAAAAGUUCUCUCUUCAGAAUUCUAAGUGGGCUCUGGCCUGUGUAUGAAGGAGUCCUCUAUAAACCACCUCCUCAACAUAUGUUUUAUAUUCCACAAAGUUUAUCUGUCUUUCCAAGUCCCUAAGGAGAGAUUUGUGAUCCCCUGCUCUCACUUUCACAAAUCCACUAAUUUAUGGCCUAUUUGUUACUUCCUAAUCCCCUGGUAAGUUUCUGUCUUCAUCCAUGAAAGCCCCUAAACCCACCCUUUUACUUGUUUAUUUUGUUCACCUGCUAACAAAAUUUUAUAGUAUGCUAACAAUCAUCAAAAUAAUAAAUUGGAAUAUUUAGUGGGAGUUGGGGGUAGAGAGAGAGUGGGAGAGAAGCAACAGAGGAAGGGACAGAAGGAAGAAAGACAGAUGAUAAUAGAUAUUUGCUGACAAAAUAUAUUUUGCUCAGAGUAAAAUCUUGCUUUCUUUUGUACUAGUUUUUAAAAAUAAUACUCCAGAAGAUCAUUUGCAUACAUCACAUUACAGUUGGGCCUCUGUAUCUGCAGCUUCCACAACCUUGGAUUCAACCCACCAUGAAUAAAAAAUAUUUUUAAAAUAAACACUGAAAACAACAACAUAACCAUAAAAAAUCAUACAAACAAAAAACCAAUGCAUAGUAUUUGUAUUGUGUUAGGUAUUACAAGUAAUCUAAAGAUGAUUUAAAGUAUAUAGGGGGAUGUGUGUUGGUGAUAUGCAAAUACUGUGGCCAUUUUAUAUAAAGGCAUCUGUGGAUUUUGGUGUUUUCUGGGGUCCUGGAACCAGUUCCACCCUGGGCACCAACCCAUCAUGUAAUUCUAACACGUAUGCUCUUACUACCUACGCUUCCUUGGCAGAAAUAUCUUGAAAAAGAAAUUUUAAUCGUAAUUUUCUUACUAUUCAAACUUACUAUGCAGGCCCAAAUACUAAGGCCCACAAGAUCUGAAAUAGAUUCAGGCUUCCCACAAUGGUGUACAAAAAGGUAACUUGUAUAAACUUCUGCCCACCCAUGACUUUGGAGUCUGAGAAACAAAAGGUUCAGAAAGUGAAAGAAGGAUUAUAUAUAAGUAUAGAAUUAAAUCUGAUCAAAUACUUUUUUUAAAGAAAGAAAAAGAAAAAAAGGGAGAAAUAGCUGGAGUAUUGUGUUUCAUGUCAGAGAGAUAACAAUUUUUUUUUCAUUUAGUCUUUUUAGGAUAGACAAUAAUUAGCAUAUAAUCUUAUGAUGUUUAUGUAUCAUUUAGUUAUAAAUAAAAACAUUCAACUAAUGGAAAUAAAAACCAGAAAUAAGUGCCUCAAGAAAGGCAAGAAAUGCUAUGGAUGUUCAAAAUGAGGAAAAAAUAGAACAGUGUGUCAUUUGACCUGAGUUUUGAAAGUAAUUCAGGAUUUGAACAGUUGCCAUGGAUUGCAUCAGUUUCUCCAAUUUCUAAAUAGGUAAGAAAUACCACAGAUUCAAGUAAGCAGAAGUUUUUGUUUUUUGGACACUUCUGGAUAGCAUAAUGUUCUUUCCUACUCUCCUCUAACACACGAUGCUGAGAAAAGAAAGCAUUUCUUAGACUCAUCCCCACUAAUAAGAAGUCAUCAGUACAUACUGGAAAUGAUAGUGCUCAUCCUCUCAGUCCUUACUCGUUUGCUGCACUGUUUCUUUUAGCUGAAGUUCUUUGAUUUAAUUUUUUAAGGUUUUUUAGUAAUUUGGAUGUUUGCCAUUUUCCCAGUCUCUAGCUAAGGAGCUCAACCUGCUCUCUAUAAGUAAGUGACACAAUUUUAUGUGCUAAAUUACUUCUCAAAAAGCAUAAUAAAAGAUGACGGUAGCUUGCUUCCACAACACUCAUUAUUUUUUGUUUCCUGUUUUCAGAAGAUAUUCUGAAAUUAUGAGUAACAUUUUACUUAUCAGCUCAAUAUUUGUUUAUUUCUAACUAGUAACUACUACUUCAUUCACAGGGUUGUGUGCACAAGUACCAUGUUACUUAAUCUCCUAGAUUAAAUAUAAAUACUACUUGAUAAAUAAAGUUAUGAAUCACAUUUUAAAAUUAAAUGCAACAUAAAAGUCUUAAAUUUGAUUGUAAGCAGGAAUGGUAAACAUCACUAAUUAGAUUGUACAGGAAAUUAAAUAUAGAUAAUAACUUUAUUUCUAUCUUGUUAUGCAUGAAUAAUACAUAUUAAUUAUGUUCUGUAUAAGUUAUGCUAAAUAGAGUAUUUUUAAGUAAUUAAAUUGAAUUUCAAAGGGACUACAUACUUUACUUAGCGUUAUAUGGAAUUUCAAAGCCAGAGUUAGACUAUACCAAGUCUUUGAAUACAAAUCUUCUGUACUCACUGCCUCUCAUUUUCAGAUUAAUAAGAUUAUCACAUUUAAGCAUCUUAAGAUGAAAAAAAUCCUACUGUUUUUGAUCUUAAAUAUUUUCUCAGAUAAUCAUAACACAGUCUGUAUUACUUUCCCAACUUUCUGAGGAAUAACAAAAUAUCAUUCUUUAUAAUUUGUCUUCACUUUUCAAAAAUAUCUGUAUCUUCAGCUAUCUUCUUUUUUCUUUUUCUUUUUUUGAAACAGAGUGUCACUCUGUCACCCAGGCUGGAGUGCAGUGGCACAAUCUUGGCUCACUGCAGCCUCUGCCUCCUGGGUUCACCAUGGUACCACCAUGCACGGCUAAUUUUUUAUUAUUUGUAUUGACAGGGUUUUCCUACCUUGCCAGGGCUAAUCUUGAACUCCUGGCCUCAAGUGAUUAUCGCACCUCAGCUUCCCAAGUAACUGGGAUUACAGGCGCCCACCACGAAACCCAGAGAAUUUUUGUAUUUUUAGUAGAGUUGGGGUUUCAUCACGUUGGCCAGGCCGGUCUCGAACUCCUGGCCUCAAGUGAUCCACCCGCCUUGGCCUCCCAAAGUGCUGGGAUUAAACACGUGAGCCACUCUACCUGGCCAUUGUAUUCUUCAACUGUUUUUCUAAGGAAGAAGAGCUUAAGACAUGAAAUCUCAGCCUUUACAAGUACUAGUAUAUUUAUGUUUUCUUUGGUAUCUUUAAUUGAUAUCUAUAUUUUCUUUGAUGGCAUUUCCACUUCUUCCUUUUAAUGAUAUAGUGUGUGUGUUUUAAAAAAUUAUAUGCAUUAAAAUUGAUUUUAUCCUGAGAAUGUUGUGACCUCUUGAGAUAACUGUUGGGUCCUAGGCAUCCUGAACCAGGAUUGAGCAUCUCUAGGGUAUUGUUAUUUUUUGUAAUUAACAAUAUGUCAAACAAUUAGUGUGUGCUAGUCACAAUUCUACAUAUAUAAGUUUCUUAUUUUUCUGUAUGACAACCUAUAAAGUUGGUAUUAGUAUCCCUAUUUUGUGAGAAAACUUAAAGAGGUUUAAGUCCUCCAGUGGAUAAAUGCUGGAGCUAGAAUUUGAACUCAGAUGUGCCUUACCCUAAAGUCAUUUUGCCUUAUUGGUAUCAACAGGGGCAUGUGUAUGAAAAAUUACUACCCUUUAUCCUGACCUUGCAAGUAUCACCAGCUAAGGUUGUUUUCUUGGUGUGCUGAUCUGUACUAAUAUCAAGCUGUGGUUUGGAGGCAGAGGUCCUCAUAAUCCUCGAUGUACAUGGCAAUUAAGUCAAUUUUAACAUACAUUUUAGCAUAGGUACUUGGCCAUCAUUCAGAUAUGUUAAGGUGAAGGAAGCUAUAUUCUCAUAUGAAAGUGAAAUUUUAAAAAAUUUAUUGGUGUUCAAUUCAUUUUCAAAUUAAAUUUUAUUCUCUACUCUUUCCUAUUCUUCUAAAAUUCAUUUCUCCAUAAAAUUUUAAAGAAUUUUUCAAAAAUAGUCCCUUAAUUUUAAAUCAGAAUUCUUGUUGAGAUAUAAAACAAGCAAACCUUAAUUUUCAGGAUGCAUUAUGGCUUAAAAAGAUCAUGACUUACCCUUUAUGUCAUCAAAAGAAGAGAUUGUCGCUUGCAACAGUGAAGACGGUGUUUUAUUUCAGAAGUUCUGCAGAAAGGGCUUGAAGGACGAUAAUACCAACAUUGGCACAACUGCCCUGUGCACUAAGAAGUACUUGCACCAAAUAAGCUUUAUGGAUAUUUUAAAAUAUGAAGUUCUGGGCUGGGCCUGGUGGCUCAUGACUGUAAUCCCAGCACUUUAGGAGGCUGAGGUUGGAUAAUCACUUGAGGCCAGGAAUUUAAGGUUAGCCCUGGCAACAUAGGGGGACCCCGUCAAUACAAAUAAUAAAAAAGUAGCUGGAUAUGGUGGUACUUGCCUGUAGUCCCAGCUACUUAAGAGGCUGAGGUGGGAGGGCUGCUUGAGUCUGGGAAGUUGAGGCUGCAGUGAGCCAUGAUUGCACCACUGCACUCUGGCCUGGGCAACAGAGUGAGAUGCUAUCUCAAAAGAAUAAAAAUAAAAAUAAAACAAAAAAAUAAAAGCUGUGAAGUUCCAUUUUCUAUUGUUUCUAUAUGAAUGACUUCCAAAUCUAAGAUUUCUUCUUUGUAGGGAUCAGGGAACUCUGUGUUAUAUAUCAACAUUGUUUAACCCACACAUAUAAAACCAGAUGAUGGCUAUUAACUAGAAAGCAUAUGAGAUCAGGUCAGAAGAACUGAUUUGCCUCUUUUCUCUAUGGAGGACAGAAAGGGUGCUGUUAAAGUAUUCUCAGUGAGAUCCUUGCUUUUUUUCUUUUUAUCCAAGAUCUCAGAUUUUAAAAAUGAGGAUGUGGUCUGGAAAAGGAUCUAAGCAAGAAUCUGGGGUAUGCUGUUUUAAAUAUCUUAAUCUCAAUUUUCCUAUAGGUCUCUAGCUUUUGGACCUGUCAAUUCUUAAUGAAUAUCUAGCUGCCAAAAGGCAAACAGGGUGCACCUCUUGAGGACAAGGAGUGUGUUUAUUUAAGAAAGAGGCAGACUAGCAGGCCACUGCCUGAGUGGAAUAUGGGUCUAUAAAAGCCACUGGAAUAAAGGAGGAAUGUGAUGUGGCUUAAUCCAGAGCUCCUCACAGAACUCUAUACCUAUGUACUGUGCCAAUGUGUAUGUAGGUUACAUAUCUAUUGUCCUGCUGCCCUCAAAGCAAAGAAAUAUGGCUUUGGGAGUAGGGGUUGUACUGGAACAGACUUUGCCCUUGUUGAGUCACUGUUGAACAAACUUUUAUAGAUUAAAAGCUAGAAAAGGCAACCACAUGUCUCUGUACAGCACUGGUAGGAUCCUAGUAAAUAUAUUGUAAUUGUGCAAUAAAUAUCUGAUAAGUGAUUGACUGAAUGAAUGAACAUCUCCACAGAUUUGGUUUCUACUGCCAAGUCAAUCUGGUACCUUACACUAAUUAUGAGCAAUCUAUUUAUUUUGCUGCUUGCAGUAGGUAUGUUGCAAAAUUCUCUUUAUGAUGGGGAUAAAUAUCUGUCAUUUAACAUGUCCUUUUUUAGAAAAUUAUUUUAACCACAAGGAAGGCUUAGUAGCAUUGCUGUAGCAAAUUGACUUCUAUUCCUUGCUUUCUGACUGUUAGACUUACAGCCAAGUAAUCUUUGUAUAAAUACCUUUGGGCAGUCAGUUGACAGAAAUAGAAGUUGUACAUUUUAGUUCCUCCUGUGUAGUAGUUGGUACAGUUCAGUUUUUUUAAAUCUCUUUUAAAGAGAUCUAUAAAUGUAAACACAAUUUUCUAUAGCUUUCUAUGGCUUGGAAGAAUGCUAAAGAUACUUUUUAAAAUCUUUAACUUUUCUAAGGGCUCAUUUAUAAAAGUAAUAAUGAAAAAACUCCCCUCUCACUCAAAAGUUUUUCUCAUUUUAUGAGUACUAUUACAUUAAACCAUAUGGAACUGCAAUUUUUAUAGGUCAAAUAUCAGCAAUUUAAAUGGUAAUCUGAUAUAAUGAUAAAUACUCUUAAAGUUGACUUUUACAGAAAUUUGCAUUUUUAACAGCUUAGCAAUACUUUAAUUCUUCCACUAAUAAUAUAUUUAUUUAUUUACUUAUUGAGACAGUGUCUCACUCUAUUGCCCAGGCUGGAGUUCAGUGACACAAUCUUGGCUCACUGCAACCUCUGUCUCCAGGGUUCAAGAGAUUCUUGUGCCUCAGCCUCCCAAGUAGCUGGGAUUACAGGUGUGUGCCACCACACCUGGCUAAUUUUUGCAUUUUUAGUAGAGAUGGGGUUUCACCAUGUUGAGCAGGCUGGUCUCAAACUUCUGACCUCAGGUGAUUCACCCAGCUUGGCCUCCCAAAUUACGGGGAUUACAGAUGCGAGCCACUGCACCUGGCCUAAUAUUAUUUUUAUUACUUGGAAAUAAACCUCAUCCCUGCUCUUAAGAGGCUAUUCUCAUCUCUGUUUUGGAAUCUAGAAAUAUCUUAUCCAAAAGAUAUAAUUUCAGUAAUAGUAAAUAUCUAUUUUCACUUGAAUAUUUCUUCUUAUUAUCACACAUUUUUUAAGAAUACUAUAAAUGACUCAAAUCUAGUUCUUUCUAUGCAUGAAAAACCCUGAUGCAAUGAUUGGUUCCAGCAUGUAUAGUUAUGUGAAUUAUUGAUAGUUAAAUUUUAUGCCUUUCAGAUUGUUAACUUCUUUUGCUACGACAACACAGCAGUACUUAGUGGUACAUUAUUCUUAAACUUAACACAUCUCAUGCCUUAAAUACAGUUAACAUUGCUGCAAAAUUUUUAUCAAUAUUGUUCCAAUUAAAUUUUAUAUGAUUACUUUAAAAAUUUGUUUUCUCUGCAUAUAGGCCUUUCAUGUCACACUUUUUUUUCUCCUCUGGAUUUGAAUUGGUUUUUUGCUCUCAAUUUAGGAAAUAUUUAGAAUUUUGUGUCAUUCAGAAGCUCCAAGCACAUAGAUACAGCUAACACUUCUCAGUGCUUUCCCAUUCUUUCUAGCUUUGUCUUAGAGAAUAAUAAAAAAGUAACUCUAACAAACAUCAAUACAUUUUACCAAAAAAAAAAAAUCACUGUCAGAUUACUUAGAUGUUAAUGCAGAAAAGUGGGAAUAUAAUGCAAAGUAUAAAAGCACCUUGAGACAUUAGUAACAAAACUAUAAAAAGCCAUAAUCA